AGAAGGGCGUCGGGCGGCCGUCGGGACGGAAGCCGGGAGGCGCUGCCGACCGCGCCUGCGACAGCGUCAGCCCUGCGCGGAGCGCCGGCCCGAUGGCGGCGGCGGCGGCGAUGGCCGAGCAGGAGAGCGCCCGGAACGGCGGCCGCAACCGCGGCGGCGUCCAGCGUGUGGAGGGCAAGCUGCGCGCCAGCGUCGAGAAGGGCGACUACUACGAGGCGCACCAGAUGUACCGGACCCUGUUCUUCAGGUACAUGUCCCAGAGCAAGCACACGGAGGCCCGGGAGCUCAUGUACUCGGGAGCCCUGCUCUUCUUCAGCCAUGGCCAGCAAAACAGUGCAGCAGACUUGUCCAUGCUGGUCCUGGAGUCCCUGGAGAAGGCGGAAGUGGAGGUGGCUGACGAGCUGCUGGAAAAUCUGGCUAAAGUGUUCAGCCUGAUGGACCCCAACUCUCCUGAGCGCGUGACCUUUGUGUCCAGAGCCCUGAAGUGGUCCAGUGGGGGCUCCGGGAAGCUGGGCCACCCCCGGCUGCACCAGCUGCUGGCCCUCACCCUGUGGAAAGAACAAAACUAUUGUGAGUCGAGGUAUCAUUUUCUGCACUCAGCGGACGGGGAGGGCUGUGCCAACAUGCUGGUGGAGUAUUCCACGUCCCGCGGCUUCCGCAGCGAGGUGGACAUGUUCGUGGCCCAGGCCGUGCUACAGUUUCUCUGUUUAAAAAACAAAAGUAGCGCAUCGGUGGUCUUCACGACGUACACCCAGAAGCACCCGUCCAUCGAGGACGGGCCUCCGUUUGUGGAGCCGCUGCUUAACUUCAUCUGGUUCCUGCUGCUGGCUGUGGACGGUGGGAAGCUGACGGUGUUCACUGUGCUGUGUGAGCAGUACCAGCCAUCCCUCCGGCGGGACCCCAUGUACAACGAGUACCUCGACCGCAUAGGACAGCUGUUCUUCGGCGUCCCGCCCAAGCAGACGUCUUCCUACGGGGGCCUGCUCGGGAACCUUCUGACCAGCCUCAUGGGCUCCUCAGAGCAGGAGGAUGGGGAGGAGAGCCCCAGCGACGGCAGCCCCAUCGAGCUGGACUGAACUGGCCAGGCCACGUGGAGACACCACGGUCGACGACGGCUGGAGGGACGUUUCAGAGGCGAGUCCUGGGUGGCUCCUCGCCUUGGGGGCUCCUGGCCCUGAGGCUGGCGGUGGCCGCAUGCCGGCGCGUGUCUGUUUCUGUGCGGCGGCUCAGGGUGGCGCGGCUGCUGCUCACUGUGCUGCUGGGACCCAAGAGUGGGGCGUCGCCCCUGCUGGCCGCCGCGUCCCCCGAGAUUGACCCACAAUAAAGCACAGGCCUUACCGCGGCGUCACCCUCUCCCACUCCUUUGUUCUGGGUCCUUUCGGGAGGGCUGAUGGGCAGCACAGGAGGCCCGUCCUCGGGGGGCUGCGCACAUCACGCUCCUUGCCGGGCGUCCGGCACAGCUGCGGUCACCAAAGCAGGUGCUGGCCCUCGGACCUGAGAGCCCAGCCAGGGCCCAUGUGGUCUGCAAAUGGGAGCGGCUGUUUUUGAACACGGGGUCAUUCUGCAGUCAGGACGAACCGGUCCCCGUCGCAGACGGAGUGCACGUGCCCUGCGCCACAUCCUCACGCUCGGUGGAGGGACGCGUGCGGCGGGACGGUGCCUACGGGUACUUGCAGCUGUGUCCCAUGUGGCAUCCCAGAGCUGCGCCCUGCUGGUCUCUGUGAGCGCCACGCUGCUGUGCUGGAAAUGCCGCUUUAAAAAGGGAUACCGUGGGACUCUGCCCGUCUCUUUCAUAACGCAAUAUUUAUUUGUAUUGGGUGAUGAUUGAUUCUUUCGACCUAACAUUUUGGGUUUUAACCAAAUAACCGGUCCAGGAGUGAGCAGCUCCGUUCUGUCAGAUGCUACUCCAAAUGUUACCAGAACGAUGACAAAAGGGGAGACGCUCUAUUUUUUCACAGUUAAAUGACAGUUGUAGAUUGAUACGCAGUUGUGCAUGGGAAGGGGAAACGCACAGCUUUAUUUACUGUAAAGUGGAAUUUCAGGAAGGCUUGUGUGAACCGUUGCGCAUAAAUAAACCCUUUCUACCGGGC